AUAACUUUAAUACGCAAUUCCUAGUAUAUACUACAGGUUUCAUUUUGCUGCAGACCUUAUUGGACUGAACAAAGGAGGAUGAAUGCGAGAAUACAGACAAAGACAAAAGAGUAUAUUUGGAAGAAGGGGUCGUGGACUCCUUGCUUCUGGUGAACAAGGGUCCUGAGCUUCUAUAGCCCUUUGUAUUUAUUGAGUAAAGGAGAUAGGGAGAAGGGGGAGGUUGUGGUCAGCUGCUUGACUUAAUGCAGGCCUGCAUGACUGUAUUCUUUGAACAGUACUCUCCAGAUGUUCCAGUAGAUAACUCCAAGGAGCAUGGCACCAGGGAGUGACUGUCCUCAGUAUACCUUCUGGUGGCAGGAGCAGAAGCAAGUUUGCCCACAUUCUGCACUCAUGAUAAACAGUUUGCUGUUUGAUCAUAUAGCCUCCAGUGGAAUGCUGAGUUGGUCACAACACUCAGGCAUUCAGCUCCCAACAUUUCCCCCUUCCUGUUUAUGCAUUAAUCAAAUAAACGUAAGGCCAGGUUGGGCAGCUCUCAUUUUGUGAUUGGUCCGUCGGAUUUUACAGACUAUGAACAGAAAACAGAGACAGAACAGCAUUACUCCAAAAACUACAUAUGAGAUGUUUGUGUGGUGCUUUAGAUAGGUCCAAGGAUUGAGGCUCUCCAGGCCUUGCUGGAAUUCGGUCCAGUCUUCUAAAGAAGGCUGAAACUCUUGAGUUUGCUUAUUUAAAUCAAGAAUUUUGUUUUGUAAUUCACCAGUAUCAAAGGUGAUGUUGGGUGUGAAAGCUCCCCGCAAAUGGGCUUUCACAAGGUCCCAUGGAUACUCGCUUUGGUUAUAUUCUACGUUGGUUACACAUAUAUGAGUGUGAUUUAAAUGAUAGCACAAUUGCUCUUUCAAUUGUAAGUUUUGUAAUUGUUCUCCUAACCAUAGAACCAUGGAUUUCAACAUUGCCACUUGUUUAUAACUCAGUGUUAAUUUUAUUCUUUAGUAGCCAUGCUUGGUUGGCUGUAUGCCUCUGCAUCCAGUUCUCCACAUACUGAGCUGUUGAAUAGAACUAUGCAAAGCUACAGAGGACAUCACAAUAGAAGUUAUUAGUGUGACCAAGGAAACAAUAGCAAAAAUUAUCAUGCCUAAGGGUCUGCGGACACGAUAAGUAUUGCUGCCUUUAAGCCAGACCUGAUCAUUUUUCUGGAGCAAGGAAAAGAGCCCUGGAAUAUGAAGAGACAUGAGAUGGUGGAAGAACCCCCAGUUAUAUGUUCUCAUUUUUCCCAAGAGUUUUGGCCAGAGCAAGGCAUAGAAGAUUCUUUCCAAAAAAUGAUAUUGAGAAGAUAUGACAAAUGUGGACAUGAGAAUUUACACUUAAAAAUUAGUUGUACCAAUGUGGAUGAGUGUAACGUGCACAAAGAAGGUUAUAAUAAACUUAACCAGAGUUUAACAACUACACAGAGCAAAGUAUUUCAAUGUGGCAAAUAUGCAAACGUCUUUCAUAAAUGUUCAAAUUCAAACAGACAUAAGAUAAGGCAUACUGGAGAGAAAGGUUUGAAAUGUAAAGAAUAUGUCAGAUCAUUUUGCAUGCUUUCACACCUAUCUCAACAUGAAAGAAUUUAUACUAGAGAGAAUUCCUACAAAUGUGAAGAAAAUGGCAAAGCUUUUAACUGGUCCUCAACCCUUACUUAUUAUAAGAGUAUUCAUACUGGAGAGAAACCCUACAAAUGUGAAGAAUGUGGCAAAGCCUUUAGUAAGUUCUCAAUCCUUACUAAACAUAAGGUAAUUCAUACUGGAGAGAAACCCUACAAAUGUGAAGAAUGUGGCAAAGCUUUUAAUCGAUCCUCAAUCCUUACUAAACAUAAGAUAAUUCAUACUGGAGAGAAACCCUACAAAUGUGAAGAAUGUGGCAAAGGAUUUAGUAGCGUCUCAACCCUUAAUACACAUAAGGCAAUUCAUGCUGAAGAGAAGCCCUACAAAUGUGAAGAAUGUGGCAAAGCUUCCAACUCGUCCUCAAAGCUCAUGGAACAUAAGAGAAUUCAUACUGGAGAGAAACCCUACAAGUGUGAAGAAUGUGGCAAAGCCUUCAGCUGGUCCUCAAGCCUUACUGAACACAAGAGAAUUCAUGCUGGAGAGAAACCCUACAAAUGUGAAGAAUGCGGGAAAGCUUUUAAUCGAUCCUCAAUCCUUACUAAACAUAAGAUUAUUCAUACUGGAGAGAAACCCUACAAAUGUGAAGGAUGUGGCAAAGCCUUUAGUAAGGUCUCAACCCUUAAUACACAUAAGGCAAUUCAUGCUGAAGAGAAGCCCUACAAAUGUGAAGAAUGUGGCAAAGCUUCCAACUCAUCCUCAAAGCUCAUGGAACAUAAGAGAAUUCAUACUGGAGAGAAACCCUACAAGUGUGAAGAAUGUGGCAAAGCCUUCAGCUGGUCCUCAAGCCUUACUGAACACAAGAGAAUUCAUGCUGGAGAGAAACCCUACAAAUGUGAAGAAUGUGGCAAAGCCUUCACCUGGUCCUCAAGCUUUACUAAACACAAGAGAAUUCAUGCUGCAGAGAAACCUUACAAAUGUGAAGAAUGUGGCAAAGGCUUUAGUACGUUCUCAAUCCUUACUAAACAUAAGAUAAUUCAUACUGGAGAGAAACGCUACAAAUGUGAAGAAUGUGGCAAAGCCUUCAGCUGGUCCUCGAUCCUUACUGAACAUAAGAUAAUUCAUACUGGAGAGAAACCCUACAAAUGUGAAGAAUGUGGCAAAGCCUUCAGCAGAUCCUCAAGCCUUACUAGACACAAGAGAAUUCAUACUGGAGAGAAACCCUACAAAUGUGAAGAAUGUGGCAAAGCUUUUAAGUCAUCCUCAACUGUUAGUUAUCAUAAGAAAAUUCAUACUGGAGAGAAUCCCUAAAAAUGUGAAGAAUGUGGUAAAUCCUUCAGCUGAUUCUCAGUCUAGUAAACAUAAGAAAAUUCAUACUGGAGAGAAAAUCUACAAAGGUGAAGAAUGUGGCAAAGCUUUUAAACAGUCCUCAAUCUUUAUUACACAUAAGAAAAUUCAUGCUGGAGAGAAACACUACAAACGUGAAGAAUGUGACAAAGGCUUCAACCGGUCCUCAAACCUUGUGGAACAUAAGAGAAUUCAUACUGGAGAGAAACCCUACAAAUGCGAAGAAUGUGAUAAAGACUUCAACUGUUCCUCACACCUUACUACUCAUAAAAGAAUUCAUACUGGAGGAAAAGCCCUACAAAUGUGAAAAACGUGGCAAAGCUUUUCAUUAGUUCUCAACCCUUACUGAACAUAAGGGAAUUUAUACAGGAGGGAAACCCUACAAAUGUGAAGAAUGUGGCAAGCCUUUUAGCUGUUCCUCAAUCCUUACUAAACAUUCAUGUAAUUCAUACUGGAGGGAAUUCCUAUAAUUGUGUGGAAUGUGGCAAAGCCUUUAACCAGUCCUUAAGGCUUACUACAUAUAAGACAACUCAUACUGGAGAGAAACCAUGCAUGUGUGAAGAAUGUGGGAAAGCCUCUAACAGAUCCUCAAUUCUUAAGAAACAUAGGCUAAUUCAUACAUGAGAGACUCUACAAACCUGAAAGAUGUGACAAUGCUUUUGGCAACACCUCAGACUUUUCUGAAUAUAAAAGAAAUCAUAUGAAUGAGAAAUCCUAGAAAUGUGAAGAAUGUGACAAAGCCUUUAAAUGGCUGUCACACUUGAUUGUAGGUAAGAUAAUAUACUGGAGAAAACUACUAGAAUAAACAAUGUGGCACACAUUUAA